CCAAAGUGCUGGAAUUACAGGUGUGAGCCACCGCGCCGGGCCGGUUUUUUCUUUUACAGAGAUGUUCACCUCAACCAAGAGUGUAUAGGAUGUGUCCUUGGGCAUGGGUGUUGAUAAUAAUUAAACCUUAAUUGGUAACUUAAUUCUAAGGGCUUUAUGGAAAUAAAUACAUUUACGCCACACCAUGGCUCUGUGGAAAGGUAUUGCUCUUUUUCUUUUUUUUUUUUUUUUUUUUUUCCUGAGACGGAGUCUCGCUCUGUCGCCCAGGCUAGAGUGCAGUGGCGCGAUCUGGGCUCAGUGCAAUAGGCCGCCUCCCAGGUUCAGGCGAUUCUCCUGCUUCAGCCUCCUAAGUAGCUGGGAUUACAGGUGCGCACCACCACGCCCAGCUAAUUUUUGUAUUUUUAGUAAAGAUGGGGUUUCACCGUUUUGGUCAGGCUGGUCUGAAACUCCUGACCUCGUGAUCCGACCGCCUUGGCCUCCGAAAAUGCUGGGAUUACAGGCGUGAGCCACCGCGCCCGGUCGCUCUUUUCCAUUUUAAAUAUGGGAGUGAGACACCUGGUGCUUAGUUCCCAGUAGAAUGAGGUACAGCUGGAGCUGGAACCUAGGCAGUUUGGGUCAGAGCCUGAGUUGAUCAUCCCUUGGAUACAUUUUCAUUGAGGUAGAGGAACUAGCUGGAAUCAGGUGGGGAAAGAGAGUUAGGACUUGAUUGAAGGGACCUUGAGAGCAAGGCUCAUAGACUUGGACUUCUGUAGGAGUCUUUUAAAAAUUUGUCAACAUCCUGUUUCACUUUUUAUAAGGAUUUUGUAUUGUGGAACCAUAUCAUUGUGGAGCAUUUUAAAAUUAGAUUAAUAGGAGGAGAAAACAUGUUUUAAAUUACCCAUGAAUCCAAGAUGUGAAGGUGCUAACUGUCUGAUACAAGAGAUGGAACUUCCAGUUCUCCUCCGUUUCUUUUUAGUCUUUCUCUGUGUCUAUUGUAUAUUUAUUUAUAAGCAUUUAAAAAAAUUGUUAUAAUAUCUUAAUGUGUUUUCCCAUAUUUCUUUAACUAUGGAAAUUUUUAAAUACUGCUAAUAGAGAAUAAACUAGUAAACUGCCAUAUUAUGUCAUGCUCAUCCAAUAUUAUUCCCAUUUGUGUUUUUUUUUUUUUUUUUUUAGACGGAGUCUCGCUCUGUCACCUAGGCUGGAGUGCAGUGGUGCGAUCUCGGCUCACUGUGAGCUCCGCCUCCCGGGUUCACACCAUUCUCCUGCCCCAGCCUCCUGAGUAGCUGGGACUACAGGUGCCGGCCACCAUGCCCGGCUAUUUUUUUGUAUAUUUAGUAGAGACGAGGUUUCACUGUGUUAGCCAGGAUGGUCUCGAUCUCCUGACCUUGUGAUCCGCCCACCUCGGCCUCCCAAAGUGCUGAGAUUACAGGUGUGAGCCACGGCGCCCAGCCCCCAUUGUUAUCAUCCUUAUGACUAUUUCCUGAUAGUUGAAAACCUUUCAUUUUUAUAUCAUUUCAAAGCUGUAGAAGAGUUGCAAAAAUAGUAUAAGGAAUUCUCAUAUACUCUUUACCCAAAUUUGCCGAUUGUUUACAUUUUUCCUGUUUGCUUUGUUGGUGGCCAUCAGCCAAAUACUACCAGGAACAUAUCUGUAACCAGAGACGAUUGUAGAUUUCUGCAGCAAGGAAGCCCACAUUCCAUGGUGAUCAUGGGGUGACUUGACUGUGGCACGUUUCAGGCAGGAUUCCUCCUUCAUUCAAACUGCAUCACCCAGGAGUCUGCAAAUUCCCCAAAGUAGGAGGAAAAAUGACCACAUUCAAGGUGAGGGGGGCGUGCCUCUCUCGCUGUUAAAAUUCCAUGUCACUACUCAUAUUUUCAUGUGUUUUUCUCUGUCAUGAGAAGACUCAAGGGGAAAACAGGCAUUUGGGGACCUGUUUGUGCCAGGUGCUUCCUUUAUCUCUUUUGUGUUGACUGCAUUUGGUUUUUGGUUUUGCUUUGUUUUGUUUUGUUACCAUUAUUUAUUUUAUGGAGUAUGAAAAUUAGUAGAAAUGAACAGUGCUCCCACUUCCUUACCUCCCCUCUCUCAAAUUAUCUGUUUUUAUCUUCUCUGCUGUUCGUCAUGUACAUUUGUAACUGUAUUUGUAUUGAUGAUAUACAUCUAAUUGUAAACUGUGCUCUUUUUAUAUGUUAUAUAAUCUUCCAUUUUUAUGGUUACAUCAUAUUCCUAUUACAUUGAUGUAUCUUUUUAUUUAUAACUACCUCACGCUCAUAGACAUAUUUUAAGCAACACUGCAGUGACAGCUUUCCUAUACAUAACCUUUUCCCACAAAAUUAAUUUUGAAAACCAUAUGCCAUUUUAGCUCAAUUUUGAAAGGGUACUUUUGAUAUGUACCACAUUGGCUGUUUUGCAGAUAGAAUAUUUUAACUAGGCACAGAACAAAAGGAUGUAACUGCUGCACCACACAAAUAUUGUUGGAGUUUUCACACUGGAAGAGCUAGAUUCUGUGUUCUCCUUGUCUCAGUCAUACUUUGCAUGUGCUUUAUUUACUGGUCUCUUCUUAUUCAUUUAUGUAGUAAGCAGUUUAACCAAAGCAGUAGAAAGCCUUCAUUUAAAAUGUCCAGUGAUACUAAGUUUUGCCAAUCACUUGUGUUCUGUUACUACAUUUACUCCUCAGCGCAGCGGAAUGAGGUUCCUGGUCUCUUCUUCUUCUUGAACAGGUGAAAUAUGAGAAACCUUCUCAGGUGUACACAGGCAACCAAAGGUCAGGAGUGUUAGCCAUUCGGCUCAGGUGAAAAAGAGAAACAAGGAGAGAGACAGAAUUCUCCAUUGAGCAACCUGUGCCCUGUGAUGUGGAUGUCUGGAGUGCCCUGUGGAGUGAUGGUGUCCCUAGUGGUGCUGCUCCUCCCUGUCCCUACUUGGUGUGACUUCUUGUCACAUGUCACUAUGACAUGGCAUCUACUCCAGGCACUGAAGUAUACUGAUUACCAUAGUUGUUAUAGAAAAUCUUUAAAUCCCUUUUGGCAAAAGAUGCCUCACACAAUGUUACCAGAAGAAAUAAUGACCUGGGGCAGAAAUGUUAGCCACGUGGAUACCUAAAGAAAAUAAAAUUCAAAAUCAAAACCUUGAGCACAGAAUAAAGGAAAAACUCCAAACAGAUAGGAACAAAGGACACUAAAAGGCCAAUGUAAAAGGAGAAGUAGAGAUGGCCAAUAACCUUGAAAAGUGAUGGUUUUCAUUUGUAAUCAAAUAAGUGAGAAUAAUAGAAUGAUUUGUUCCCCAAAUCAGAUUACCAAGACUGUGGGAAUACUUAUAACCUGCUCUUGGUCAUGAUAAAGAGAAGCAAAGUACUUGUAUUCUGUUCAAAGAUUAUGGAGGAGGCAGUGACCUUCAAGGAUGUGGCUGUGGUCUUCACUGAGGAGGAGCUGGGGCUGCUGGACCCUGCCCAGAGGAAGCUGUACCGAGAUGUGAUGCUGGAGAACUUCAGGAACCUGCUCUCAGUGGGGCAUCAACCGUUCCACCAAGAUACUUGCCACUUCCUAAGGGAAGAAAAGUUUUGGAUGAUGGGGACAGCAACCCAAAGAGAAGGGAAUUCAGGAGGCAAGAUCCAAACUGAGUUGGAGUCUGUUCCAGAAGCAGGAGCACAUGAAGAGUGGUCCUGCCAGCAAAUCUGGGAACAAAUUGCAAAAGACUUAACCAGGUCUCAGGACUCUAUCAUAAAUAACUCUCAGUUCUUUGAAAAUGGUGAUGUCCCCUCCCAGGUUGAAGCAGGACUACCCACAAUUCAUACAGGACAGAAACCUUCCCAGGGUGGGAAGUGUAAACAGUCCAUCAGUGAUGUUCCCAUCUUUGAUCUUCCUCAGCAGUUAUACUCAGAAGAGAAGUCUUAUACAUGUGAUGAGUGUGGAAAAAGCAUCUGUUACAUCUCAGCUCUUCAUGUUCAUCAGAGAGUCCACGUGGGAGAGAAACUCUUUAUGUGUGAUGUGUGUGGCAAGGAAUUUAGUCAAAGCUCACAUCUGCAAACUCAUCAGAGAGUCCACACUGGAGAGAAACCAUUCAAAUGUGAGCAAUGUGGGAAAGGUUUCAGUCGUAGAUCAGCACUUAAUGUUCAUCGUAAAUUACACACAGGAGAGAAACCUUACAUUUGUGAGGCAUGUGGGAAGGCCUUCAUUCAUGAUUCCCAGCUUAAGGAACAUAAGAGAAUCCAUACUGGGGAGAAACCAUUCAAAUGUGAUAUAUGUGGUAAGACCUUCUAUUUUAGGUCAAGACUUAAGAGCCAUUCCAUGGUUCACACAGGAGAAAAACCAUUUAGGUGUGAUACAUGUGAUAAGAGCUUUCAUCAGAGAUCAGCACUUAAUAGGCAUUGCAUGGUCCACACAGGAGAGAAACCGUACAGAUGUGAGCAGUGUGGAAAAGGCUUUAUUGGUAGGCUAGAUUUUUAUAAGCAUCAGGUGGUCCACACAGGAGAAAAACCAUAUAAUUGUAAAGAAUGUGGGAAGAGCUUCAGAUGGUCCUCAUGCCUUUUGAACCAUCAGCGAGUCCACAGUGGAGAAAAAAGCUUCAAAUGUGAAGAAUGUGGAAAGGGAUUUUAUACAAAUUCACAACUGUCUUCCCAUCAGAGAUCCCACAGUGGUGAAAAGCCAUAUAAAUGUGAGGAGUGUGGGAAGGGCUAUGUUACUAAGUUUAAUCUUGACUUGCACCAGAGGGUCCACACGGGAGAGAGACCUUAUAAUUGUAAGGAAUGUGGGAAGAACUUUAGCCGGGCCUCAAGUAUUUUGAAUCAUAAGAGACUCCACUGCCAGAAAAAACCAUUCAAAUGUGAGGACUGUGGAAAGAGGCUUGUACACAGGACAUACCGUAAAGACCAGCCGAGAGACUAUAGUGGGGAAAACCCAUCCAAAUGUGAGGAUUGUGGGAGACGCUACAAGAGGCGCUUGAAUCUGGAUAUACUUUUAUCAUUAUUUCUAAAUGACACAUAAUUGUUCAUAUUUAUGGGGUACAACGUGCUAUUUUAAUGUGUGCAUACAAUUUAUAGUGAUCCAAUCAGUGUAAUUGGUGUAUCUGUUACCUCAAACAUUUACCAUUUCUUUGUGUUGGAAAAUUCAAAAUCCAUUUGAGAGGAGUUGGUAGACAGCAAGGGAAGGGUCCCUGGAGACCCCCAGCCAAACGGGUCAGUGUCUCAUCCCCACAUAACACAAAAAGCAGCCUGGGGAAGACAAUCAAGCUACAGGCACUGAUAAGGGAACUAGCACAGGGGAUUGUGCCUGGAGACAUGCCCAUGGCUGCACAGAUAGAAGAACCUCCAGCCCAUUCAGGUAAAAACUCGCACAAACCUCCGGCUCACUCAGUUAAGGGAACAAGACCAGACACAGAAAUGCCUUUGUCCUUUGUAUAAUCAGCAGGCUCCGAGGAAAAAGUUUCUUCUUUUGUGGGCAUGAACACAGUGGGCUUCAGUAGGUUCAGGUUGGCACUUUCUUUUGUGGAAAAGGAAAAGCCCAGCCUCUGUAAAUCAUCACUUCAGCUCCUGAUUGGUCCCAGGCCAAGCUGAAUAGCCCUUAGGAAUAAUCACUUCAACUCCUGAUUGGUCCCGGGCCAAGCUGAAUAGCCCUUAUGAAUCAUCACUUCGGUUCCUGAUUGGUCCCGGGCCAAGGUCCCAGACCAAGCUGAAUCACGCUUUCUCCAAGACAGCCCGCAGGCUAAGUGCAUUCCUUCCCCUUCCCAGUCCAUAAAAACCCCGGACCCCAGCCUCAUACUGGGCAACUUAUUUGGAUCCCCAUCUCCACUGUGGAGAGCUUUUUUCUUUCACUUAUUAAACUUUUACUCCAAUUUCA